GCUCGUGUCCCUGUCAUAUUUUCCACUCUCCACGAGGUCCUGCGCGCUUCAAUCCUGCAGGCAGCCCGGUUUGGGGAUGUGGUCCUUGCUGCUCUGCGGGUUGUCCAUCGCCCUUCCACUGUCUGUCACAGCAGAUGGAUGCAAGGACAUUUUUAUGAAAAAUGAGAUACUUUCAGCAAGCCAGCCUUUUGCUUUUAAUUGUACAUUCCCUCCCAUAACAUCUGGGGAAGUCAGUGUAACAUGGUAUAAAAAUUCUAGCAAAAUCCCAGUGUCCAAAAUCAUACAGUCUAGAAUUCACCAGGACGAGACUUGGAUUUUGUUUCUCCCCAUGGAAUGGGGGGACUCAGGAGUCUACCAAUGUGUUAUAAAGGGUAGAGACAGCUGUCAUAGAAUACAUGUAAACCUAACUGUUUUUGAAAAACAUUGGUGUGACACUUCCAUAGGUGGUUUACCAAAUUUAUCAGAUGAGUACAAGCAAAUAUUACAUCUUGGAAAAGAUGAUAGUCUCACAUGUCAUCUGCACUUCCCGAAGAGUUGUGUUUUGGGUCCAAUAAAGUGGUAUAAGGACUGUAACGAGAUUAAAGGGGAGCGGUUCACUGUUUUGGAAACCAGGCUUUUGGUGAGCAAUGUCUCGGCAGAGGACAGAGGGAACUACGCGUGUCAAGCCAUACUGACACACUCAGGGAAGCAGUACGAGGUUUUAAAUGGCAUCACUGUGAGCAUUAAAAGAGCUGGAUAUGGAGGAAGUGUCCCUAAAAUCAUUUAUCCAAAAAAUCAUUCAAUUGAAGUACAGCUUGGUACCACUCUGAUUGUGGACUGCAAUGUAACAGACACCAAGGAUAAUACAAAUCUACGAUGCUGGAGAGUCAAUAACACUUUGGUGGAUGAUUACUAUGAUGAAUCCAAACGAAUCAGAGAAGGGGUGGAAACCCAUGUCUCUUUUCGGGAACAUAAUUUGUACACAGUAAACAUCACCUUCUUGGAAGUGAAAAUGGAAGAUUAUGGCCUUCCUUUCAUGUGCCACGCUGGAGUGUCCACAGCAUACAUUAUAUUACAGCUCCCAGCUCCGGAUUUUCGAGCUUACUUGAUAGGAGGGCUUAUCGCCUUGGUGGCUGUGGCUGUGUCUGUUGUGUACAUAUACAACAUUUUUAAGAUCGACAUUGUUCUUUGGUAUCGAAGUGCCUUCCAUUCUACAGAGACCAUAGUAGAUGGGAAGCUGUAUGACGCCUAUGUCUUAUACCCCAAGCCCCACAAGGAAAGCCAGAGGCAUGCCGUGGAUGCCCUGGUGUUGAAUAUCCUGCCCGAGGUGUUGGAGAGACAAUGUGGAUAUAAGUUGUUUAUAUUCGGCAGAGAUGAAUUCCCUGGACAAGCCGUGGCCAAUGUCAUCGAUGAAAACGUUAAGCUGUGCAGGAGGCUGAUUGUCAUUGUGGUCCCCGAAUCGCUGGGCUUUGGCCUGUUGAAGAACCUGUCAGAAGAACAAAUCGCGGUCUACAGUGCCCUGAUCCAGGACGGGAUGAAGGUUAUUCUCAUUGAGCUGGAGAAAAUCGAGGACUACACAGUCAUGCCAGAGUCAAUUCAGUACAUCAAACAGAAGCAUGGUGCCAUCCGGUGGCAUGGGGACUUCACGGAGCAGUCACAGUGUAUGAAGACCAAGUUUUGGAAGACAGUGAGAUACCACAUGCCGCCCAGAAGGUGUCGGCCGUUUCCUCCGGUCCAGCUGCUGCAGCACACACCUUGCUACCGCACCGCAGGUGAGCGGGUGGGAGGACACGAGGUUUGUCACGCACUGAUGGAGGGUCUAUCAUUGCGUGGUGGCUCACAGCUGGAGGAGGACACGUUUCAUCGGGGCCGUCUGCUCUGAAGCUGGCAGUUGCGUACUAGUGAGAGGAUCUGUUGUGUUUGUUGUCAUUUGUUUGCUUCGAUCAGAGCUGCUUCUUCAGGGAAACACACGGCUUCUGCAGAAGGCCCUCUUUAGCCUAUGGGCUUAUUGACACAUGCCCACUCACUGAGGCCUGGAUGGAUACAGCACUUGGGCCCCUUGAGAACAGGACAUGGAGGGUUUUAGAAAUGGCAGUGGACAUGCCCGGAAGUUUGCCCAUGAUGUGGCACCCAUAGAGUCUGAGAUGGGAGCCUGUGCUGUCGGGGGACCACAGGAGGGCAGUCUAGCACCAGGAGAGGGUUGGCAAGGAUAGCAGUAUUUGUCCACGCCUGUCCAGUGUCUUCAGGGCCCCAUGCUCAGGGGUCAUUUGCUGUGUCUGCGUCUCUCUCACUCUGUCAGUGCAGACAAAGAGCUGCAAACACAGCCUUAGCACUUUGCUUCCAGAAGCAAGUUAAAAGUCACCUAGACCAGUGGGGACCCACGGGAGUGGCCAUGACUGCCUCUUGGUCACCCUUCCAUGUUUGAGAGGCUUUAUCUGUCAAACUAAAGCAAGCAGGAAUUCCUUUUCUCUCUCUUUUAGACACAUGUCAACCAGAAUUCUGAGCAGCCUGUGAGAGACGCAAUUAGCACACAGAUGAUAGAAUUAUAGUCCAAGCAAGGCAAAGUCAGUUUCCAAUGAGCCAAUGUGCCCUUGUCACAGGCCAAUUUAUAACUUAAUGAUUAAAGGUUUUUAAUACUAAAAAUUAGCUGUAAACCCUCAUCACUUUUUUCCAAGACCCUGGCCUGAGGGAAUUAGGCAUAGCUCAACCUUCUGAAGCUGUGGGUUGUUGACACUGAGACUUAGUAAGCAGUCAGUGGGGGCUGGAAGGGAGUCAGCCCUGAGAGCCAGCCGGCAGGGGCGAGAGAGGGAGCCAGAGGGUGUCAGGAGGCCUGUGGUCUUAGGAUGGCAUGGGGAGCAGGGUGGGUUAGGAGGUGCUGUGCCCUCGUUCACAGGCGAUGGGUGGUACCCAGUGUGGGAUGGACUUUCAGGUGCUAAGGAACCCACUCCUGUCUUUGAAGAGUUUAUGUUCCAAGGUGACCUCACAUUACACAUUUGUUUAGCAUCCUAUGGAGGCCUCGACUUGACAUUGGUCCACUCUUUAUUUAACAUUUGCUUUUUAAAAUUUUUAUUUCGGUAAACUAUAUGAACAUAAAAUUCACCAUUUUAACAAUUUUUAAGUGGCAUUAAGUACAUUCACACUGUUGUGCGGCCAUCACCACCAUCCAUUCCAGAAUUGUUUCAUCCUCUCAAGCUGAAAUUCUGUGCCCAUUAAGCUAUGCCUCCCUAUUGCCUUCCCAUUGCCUUCCCAUUGCCUCCCCAUUGCUCUGAGGUAGGACAUAAAAUACAUUUUAAGAAUAACAGCAUUAAAAAAUGGCUACUAUAAUUCAUUACUACUAUUACAUUUUUGAUACUUUUCAAUAAAAAGAAAGUAGUGACACAUGUUGGAAAGAGGGAAGCUUUUUGACUUAUAAAACUCCAGUUAAAGAAUUUACCAACAGUGCUGGUCUCCGGGAAGUCAGAGGUUUCCAGAAAAUACCUUUUCGUCUGACGGGUCAGCUUUCUAUUUUGCUGACAGCCUCGACUGAUGUCCUGUGAGUGUGGUCAUUCAUUUAUAAAUAAUUAAUUGCUAGAGAAUCCAUUUUCUAAAAUUCACAGGCACACCCUUCAGAGAGGACACGUCCCCGUACCUCUCCCACUCUCCCCACACUGUGGCUGCCUCUGGCUGCCUCCAUCCUGCAGAGGGAAAUGGCUGGGAAGGAAGGGGGAAGGGUGCUGAGAUGCCCUCAAAUCUGAAUGGGGUGGGUGUAUUCCCCAAAUCCUCACCAAACCACGAGCCAGUGACCACUCACCCUUUGCGGUCCAGAUCUUACUGCCCCGGGGUUAGUCAAGUGGCCAGAGGUGGUGCCCACUGCCCUCAGGGGGUUUCCUGGCGUGGCCUGGUCUCACAUGCACUCCGCAGAAGGAAGGACGAAGCGUCCUCAGCCAGCCCGCAGCCACCCUGCCCACUCCAGCACUGCAGGCAGCCUUCAGAGACCAGCCCAGAGAAGAGAACGGCAGCGAGUGAGGGGACAGAGUGCGGAACAGAUCAGUAAUGCCCAUUUUCCUCUUGGGUGCAAUAGGAGAAACAGCCUGUUUUAAUUAAACUAGCGAAUCCUCCAUGAGGAAUAACGACUCUCAUGUUGGAGAGAGAAAUCGAGAUGCAAAGAAACUUUUUAAAGUUCUACUAAUUCCUAAUGAAAUAAUAGGGAUGCAAUGCAGCAAGAAUACAAAUAAUUGAAGUAGCCUGGCAUCACCGCUGACAUGUAGGCAGGUUGGCAGGUAACAGCUCCGCUCAUGGUCUCAAGUCCAAAUUUGUAUAAGAAAGGAGGUUUAAGAGUUCAACGGCUAAGGGACAAAAAGGUAGUUUAUGGGAACGCUGAAGGCCACCCUCAAUUCUCUCCCGUUUCUCCAGCUGGGCUUGGCGCAAAUAUGAGGUCAAUGGGGUCCUAUCCCUAGCCCUUGGGGGUGGGCUCCAGAAUUCUACUCCAAGCAAAGUGAAGUCAGUUUCCAAGGAGCCAGUGUGCCUUCAUCACAGGCCAAUUUAUAAUUUAAUGAUUCACAAAGUUUUUUAAUACUAUGAAUUAGCUGUAAACCCUCAUCACUCCUUUCCAAGACCCUGGCUUGAGGGAAUUAGAGACCCCCCUGGGAAUCCCCAGGGACUGACCUGGAGGUAGGGCUGCGAGCGGAGAUUGGACCAGAGAGGUGAAAUACAGGUGCUGAGUCGCUGGGUUACCUUUACAUUCACCUUCCCAUAAUGACUGAGUCAGCCACAAAACCCACUACCUUUGGUAUCUCCCCUCAAAUACCCUGAGUCGGCUCAUGAGAGAGGCCCUGGGAAAGACCCAGUCACAUUAAAUAAAGGGACCGGGAAGGUGUGGUCUUUCCCCGGAGGACCAAGCAAGAUGAAGAUAUACAUGUGAAAAGUGCUUGGCAAACCGUGGGAUGCCAUGAGGAGCUGGCCUGCCAAAAUAUGGAAUGUGCUCAGGGAGCCUCAGUCCCCAGGGCCCCCCACACCCAUCAGCACCCCAUAGUGACGCAGACCACUUCCUGCCACGUCAUGGUUGGUUGACCUUUCCUCGGCACUUGGUCCUGUUUUUUAUUUAUAAACUUCCCUCUAACACAUGCUUGUUUGGUAUUGAUCUGGGGCUGUGUAAAGUGGAAAAUUCCUUCCUGGUUUCCUUGAAGAACAGAGGCUGUUCCAGAUGAGGUCUGGAGUGAGCUACAGAGGGUGAUGCUGGCUUUAGGAGUGGUGGCUGCUGGGUCUGAAUGUUAGAGGCCACACAUCUCCAGUAGUAAUAUUAUUCUGGGAGAUGGGAACUCUGUGUGUGGAUGUCCCCUCCCAUACACCCAGGAACUUCUGAGAAAUGCUGCUGUUCACUAAUACAAUUCCACCCUCAUCUCCCAGGCUGUCCCUGGAGAGGAGCUCUCCACUUGAGAAGGACCUCAGAGCCCUGGCUCUUGUCAUCCAAAUUCACCUUUCCUCUGGGGCUCUUAUAGGAAAGGUGAGAGUUGACACUGCUCACCUGUGAUCCUCUGGCAUAACCACCUUGCAAAGAUAACCCAAGAGAAAUGGAAGCCUCAGGGAUAUACCACCAGAUGAACUGACGGCAAGGUGGAGGUUUUCGCAUUCCCAUGGCAGGUUUCCUUAUCAGCCCCCAUCUCCCACCACAUCAGAAAAGGAGUAAAUAGAUCUUUCCUGAUUUCAGGCCCAGAACUAGGCUCAAGAAGAAAGAAGUGUACUCUCACGACUGGCUAAGACUUGCUGGACUGACACCUAUGGCUGGAAGAUGACUUGUUUUGCUCCAUGUCUCCUCAUUCCUACACCUAUUUUCUGCUGCAGGAUGAGGCUAGGGUUAGCAUUCUAGACACCCAGUUGAGCUCAGGCGUAGAGAAGAGGAGGAUGGGAUAAGAACUGGGGCCAUCCCCAUGUCAUGGUGGGUGAGAGCUGGGGCCAUCCCCGUGGUCAUGGAGGGUGAGAGCUGGGGGUUAUCCCCAUGGUCAUGGAGGGUGAGGGCUGGUCGGGGGAGGCAUCCCCAAGUCAUGGUGGGUGAGAGCUCGGAGCAUCCCCAUGUCAUGGUGGGUGAGAUCUGGGGGUAUCCCUGUGUCAUGGUGGGUGAGGGCGGGUGGUCAUCCACAUGGUCAUAGUGGGUGAGAGCUGGGGGUAUCCCUACAUCAUGGUGGGUGAGAGCUGGGAGCAUCCCCAUGUCAUGGUGGGCGAGAUCUGGGGGGUAUCCCCACGUCAUGGUGGAUGAGAGCUGGGGGAAUCACCAUGUCAUGGUGGGUGAGAUCUUGGGGGAUCACCUGUCAUGGUGGGUGAGAGCUGGGGGGAUCACCUGUCAUGGUGGGUGAGAGUUGGGAUUCAUCCCCAUGUCAUGGUGGGCUGAGCCCACAUGGAAGCCUGUGCUUGGACAGCGUAUGCCCUUUUCUCUGUUUUUCCACAAUGAACAAUUAAACUGUAAAUGUUAAAAAUAUCAGUAAUUUGUGAAAUAAAUUUUAUUCUCAUUUGAGCAACAUAAA